AGUCCCCGCUGAGACUGAGCAGACGCCUCCAGGAUCUGUCGGCAGCUGCUGUUCUGAGGUCACACAGCUCAUGAGGGGUGGAACUAGAUUCACCCUAGGCCUCGCUGAUCUCUGUACAACGGGGGCCAGAGCUCUUCUGAGGAAGGCAGGCUUCCCUUUGUACCUGCACUGACUUUUUUCUCCUUUUGGAGGGAGAGCAGAGACCAUGUCUGACAUAGAAGAGGUGGUGGAAGAGUACGAGGAGGAGGAGCAGGAAGAAGCAGCUGUUGAAGAAGAGGAGGACUGGAGAGAGGACGAAGACGAGCAGGAGGAGGCAGCGGAAGAGGAUGCUGAAGCAGAGGCUGAGACCGAGGAGACCAGGGCAGAAGAAGAUGAAGAAGAAGAGGAAGCAAAGGAGGCUGAAGAUGGCCCAAUGGAGGAGUCCAAACCAAAGCCCAGGUCGUUCAUGCCCAACUUGGUGCCUCCCAAGAUCCCCGAUGGAGAGAGAGUGGACUUUGAUGACAUCCACCGGAAGCGCAUGGAGAAGGACCUGAAUGAGUUGCAGGCGCUGAUCGAGGCUCACUUUGAGAACAGGAAGAAAGAGGAGGAGGAGCUCGUUUCUCUCAAAGACAGGAUCGAGAGACGUCGGGCAGAGCGGGCCGAGCAGCAGCGCAUCCGGAAUGAGCGGGAGAAGGAGCGGCAGAACCGCCUGGCUGAAGAGAGGGCUCGACGAGAGGAGGAGGAGAACAGGAGGAAGGCUGAGGAUGAGGCCCGGAAGAAGAAGGCUUUGUCCAACAUGAUGCAUUUUGGGGGUUACAUCCAGAAGACAGAGCGGAAAAGUGGGAAGAGGCAGACUGAGCGGGAAAAGAAGAAGAAGAUUCUGGCUGAGAGGAGGAAGGUGCUGGCCAUUGACCACCUGAAUGAAGAUCAGCUGAGGGAGAAGGCCAAGGAGCUGUGGCAGAGCAUCUAUAACUUGGAGGCAGAGAAGUUCGACCUGCAGGAGAAGUUCAAGCAGCAGAAAUAUGAGAUCAAUGUUCUCCGAAACAGGAUCAACGAUAACCAGAAAGUCUCCAAGACCCGCGGGAAGGCUAAAGUCACCGGGCGCUGGAAAUAGAGCCUGGCCUCCUUCACCAAAGAUCUGCUCCUCGCUCGCACCUGCCUCCGGCCUGCACUCCCCCAGUUCCCGGGCCCUCCUGGGCACCCCAGGCAGCUCCUGUUUGGAAAUGGGGAGCUGGCCUAGGUGGGAGCCACCACUCCUGCCUGCCCCCACACCCACUCCACACCAGUAAUAAAAAGCCACCACACACUGA